ACAACACAGCUAACACAAGGCCCCGCAGGCAGGACUCUGGGACAGACGCAGGCCAGCUGCCCAGAGCCCAGACCAAGCAUGGACGCCGUGGAUGCCACCAUGGAGAAACUCCGGGCACAGUGCCUGUCCCGCGGGGCCUCGGGCAUCCAGGGCCUGGCCAGGUUUUUCCGCCAACUAGACCGGGACGGGAGCAGAUCCCUGGACGCUGAUGAGUUCCGGCAGGGUCUGGCCAAACUCGGGCUGGUGCUGGACCAGGCGGAGGCAGAGGGUGUGUGCAGGAAGUGGGACCGCAAUGGCAGCGGGACGCUGGAUCUGGAGGAGUUCCUUCGGGCGCUGCGGCCCCCCAUGUCCCAGGCCCGGGAGGCUGUCAUCGCAGCUGCAUUUGCCAAGCUGGACCGCAGUGGGGACGGCGUCGUGACGGUGGACGACCUCCGCGGGGUGUACAGUGGCCGUGCCCACCCCAAGGUGCGCAGUGGGGAGUGGACCGAGGACGAGGUGCUGCGCCGCUUCCUGGACAACUUCGACUCCUCUGAGAAGGACGGGCAGGUCACACUGGCGGAAUUCCAGGACUACUACAGCGGCGUGAGUGCCUCCAUGAACACGGAUGAGGAGUUCGUGGCCAUGAUGACCAGUGCCUGGCAGCUGUGAGCAGCUCCGGCUCAGCCCUGCUGCCCUGGCCUGUCACUCCCCACCCCUGCCGGAGACCUCCCUUCCCUGGGCCCCUUCUCUCCUGGGCAGCCACACCACAGAGCGGGGAGGGGCAGGUGGGGGAAUGGAGGCUGCAGGACUGGCUAGACCAGGUCCCUGCCGGUCCACCAGGCGGAGGUGGGACAAAGGUCCUAACAGGAGUCACUGGCUCAGGACCCCAGGGAGAAACGCUCUCCCCACCCACGCCAUGCUGACCAGAGAUCUUGCAGCCCCUGUGGAUGCCCCCGCCGAGGUCCCCCGAUCCCCGCACCCGGACUGCU